AUGCGGUGGGGUAGGCGGUCGGGAAAGCCCCAAAGGGGAAACCUGAGGGAGGCAGGAAGUGGGUGGGAUGGGCGUGGAAAUGACCAGGGCCUCAUCCUGUUCCUCGCACUGCCUCCUCCGAAACACCAGCCCUCUGGCGGAGGGGCGGUGGGGGGACCGAGCUCGGGUCGAGUCGGGGACUCCGGCGGCGCGCGCAGGCGACGGGGGGAGCUCCAGGGAUUUGAACGCAAACAAAGCGGCGGCGCGGGGAGCGUGGCGAGCCCGGCCUGCGGACGCCCCCUGUCGGCCCAGAGCCCCGGCGCGGGAGAGCGGGGGCUGCGCCCCAGACCAGCCCCCCAAAACGCCCGCGGCCUCAUCUCGGCUCCUUACCCGAGGAUCGGGCCGCACCCCGUGGCGUGCUCCGAGGAUCCGCCCGGCAGCGGUGCUCCCACCCGCAGCUCCCCCCAGGGCGAGGAAACGGGCAGCCGGGAGGAGGGGUUGGGGGGAGGGGUGCGGGAUCCAGGCGGGGCACCCCACACCCUCGCCCACCCCGAGCGGCCAGCCGUGGACCGCGGCCCUCCCUGCAGGGCGAGCGCUCCAGCCGGGGACGGCGCGGCCCGGCUCGGCCCGGGGGCCUGGCUUUCCGGGACAACCCGCCUCCCCAGCGGAAUGGGCGGGCGGGCGGGGGGCCGCGGCAGGGAAAUCCGAUCCCACAACAUCGGCCUCCCUCCAAGCCCGCCCCAAACUUUCCAUCGGGGGUGGGAGCGCCGAGGGCAGUCCAGGAGCCUGGCGAGGAUCCCGGCCGCGGACCGGACCGCGCGAGGAACCCUCGCUGGCGCGCCCCUCCGGCCCCGGGGCUGCGGGGCUGCAGGUGCUGUGCGCCCCACUCCCGAGACCCUGCGAAGCAGCCGCGGGGGUCGCAGGAAGGAUCCCCGCGUACAGCCGUCUCCGCCGCCGCGGCUCCCCGCGCCCCAGCCCCUGUCCCUCCCGCGUCCGGCAGCCCCUGCCCAAGCAAAGGGACAAAGCGGCGGCUCCGGGGCCCCGCGGCUCCAGCCUCACGCAAGCCCGGCCUCGCUCACCUAUUGCGCGCAGCUCCAGUCCCCGGGCGCCGCCCUCGCGUUCGGCUCUGACCGCCGUCCACCCCUGCCCCCGCGUCGCCGCCUGCCCGCGCUCGCCCGCCAGCCCUCCGCGGCCUCUCUGCCACCGCCCCUCCGUCCCCGCCCGGCUCCGCGCCCCUAGGCUCGGGCUCCCCGCGCCACCACGGCGGGCGCCGGCUCUUUCUCCAGCGCGGCCGCGGCUCUCCGCCCCCUUCCCCUUGACGUCAGGCUGGGGGGGUCGAGCGGAGGCCGGGGGCGGGCCGCGAAGGCUCGCUCAGGAGGGGGCUGCGACCCGCAGCGACCUGUGGACCCGCCCGCUCUCCGCCCGGGGGCUCGGACCUCCGCCUCUCUGGGUGCCCGGACCUCAACCCCUCCGGGUGUCCAGCAGCCCCGGGGCUCGGAGUCGCGGGCUGCGCCACAGCGCCUGGAGGGAGGUGGGGCGGGGGAGGGACUCCGGGUAUGGCCACGGGGGAAUCACACUCACCCGAUCUUUCUGAAGUGUCCCCCGAAGACUCCGGGCGGGCUGGGCUGGGGAGAGGGACUCCCGACCGUGCAGUUGCAGGAACGACCGCGGGCGAGCCACGUCGAGGCGAGUAUCCAGGGGAGGCACGCUGGGGGAACCGAGGCGUCUUUUGGGGCGGACCAGAGGGGUCUGCCGUUUGGCCCCCAAUUCUGCCUCUUUCUAGGCCCCGAGGACCACUGGUCCCUGCCCUCAAGUCUGGAAAGGGCUUCACCAGCCAGGAAGACCCUUCAAUCAACAGAAAGGGCCUGCUCCUGCUUCUCACGCUUUGGGCAAAGCGCCUAUCCCCAGAAAAUGACUCCUCGUGCCACUGGAAGGCUGAUUAACAAGUGGCAUGAGCCCUACUGUUCAGAUGAAAGGGGCUGUGGGGAGCCACGCUGCAGAACCACCGCCACCUUCAGAACCACCAGCCUCCGCCCACAGCCACUCCUAGAAGCAACUUGUAGCUCUGGCCUCAUGGGCGGUGCAGCGUCUUUCCUGCCAGCUGGUCCUCUGAGCUGGGCAGGUGGUUAGAAGAGGUGGUCCUCAUGGAGGACACCCCACGGGCACCUGGAGACAGAUGCUACCUCCUGGCUAGGGGCAAAAGGCAGAGGUGAAGGGGCUUGACGUCCUGAGGUUUGGAGGUAACUUUAAGCCAGGGUGCAGUCCUGGAGGGGAGGAACACUUCAGGCUGCGUCAGCAGAUCUGGAUUAUAAAUCAGUCCGACAGCA